GUCUGCAUCAGGAAGGCCCAAGGGUCCAACGAGCUAAGCUGAGCCCGGUGGCCGGCGAGGCACCACCAGCAGCCCAGACUACGGUCCCCCAGGAGGCGCCCCGGGAGCUCCGAGGACUCGCCCCGCGUCGCGCGGUCCUGCGCCCCGCUCGUCCCAACCAGCCUCCCCUACCACCGACAUCUGUUACUUCAAAGAGGACUUCACCGCCGCGCUCCCCACGUCCGCUGCUAGGCCCAGGAGCGCCGUCCACAGCGCCGUCGAGGCGAUGGUCAGCCGGCCCCGCAGCCCCAGCGCCUUCCCUGCUCCCUGGUGGGGACAGCAGCCAGGAGGACCCGGCCCUGCCAAGCGCCUCCGAUUGGAGGAGCCCGCGGGCCCCGAACCCCGCGCGGCACCCAGCCUGGAAGACCCGGCGGGGGACCCGGCCGUGGACGCGCUCACCUCCAUAGUGGUCCUGGCCGCGGGCUGUGCCCUGCGUGUGCCCCUGGACGACGUCGACCUGGUGCUGGAGCCCGCACCAACGUCGAUCCUGCGAGUGUCUCUCGGUGGACACACCCUCAUCCUGAUCCCAGAGGUCCUCCUGAGCUCCGUCGACGAACGCUCAGGAGCGCAGCACGACUCGUCUGCCGGGCUGGAAGUGGACGUUUUCCUGGGCGCUGUCAGGGAGGACGUCGUCGUCGAGCUGGAAUUCUGCGCAUCUGUCCCAGAGAUCGCCGCCCAGGAAGAGGCCUACGAGGAGGACGCGGACCCCGAGUUCCCGGAGCUCCGGAUGGACUCCCCAACCGGCUCAGCCGCUGGGCUCUACCCCUCCUCUAGAAGUAUGUUCAUCCCCUACCGGGAGGGCCCCAUCCCAGAACCCUGUGCUCUGGCCCCCAACCCCAGUUCAGAGAGACGUUCUCCACGCCCCAUCUUUGACCUGGAAUUCCGCCUUCUGGAGCCUGUCCCCAGCUCACCUCUCCAACCUCUACCUCCCUCUCCGUGCGUGGGGAGUCCAGGUCCCCACGCGCGCUCGCCGCUCCCGGAACGCCCUCCGUGCAAGGCCCGGAGACGCCUGUUCCAGGCAUAGACCCCCACCCCCACGUACACACAACAAUCCUGGCCGCUCUGCUGGAGGCCCUCUAGGAUUGCGGGAAUCUCUCACAUUGAGUAUCCAACAACCUGGAAAUUGGGCACCGCGUGUUCGGACAAUUGCUUUUUCGCUGCACACUACCGAUAGUAGGAGAUGAAGACGUCAGCAAGAAAAGGUAUAUUCUAGACCUCAUCUUUAAAUAGAAAAUCUGCGCAAGGAUACCAGAAAAUGUGUCCAGAUUUCUGGGCUUCUUUACAAGGUCAUAUUCAGAUCCCUUCAUUCUCCCUCGUUUUGCAUCAGUUGUUUCUCUCAAAUUCCAGUCUUUCUCCAGCAUCAUACUGCCACUCCCGUUUCUCCCCAAACCAAGAAAUCACCAGAUCUCUUACGUUGUUAGUUACCUUGCAUUUUUUUCCCAUGAAUUUUGGAAGACUUAGCCAUGGCUUUUCUUGGGGUUUUUCCAACUGCUCUCCAAGGAAACUGCCAAAUAGUAUGCUUACUAUACAAGACUGUAUGUUGCUUCUUCCUAGGAACCCCUUAUCCUGCUGAAGUUUUCUUCUAGUCUUCUAAUUCUAAAUGAAAAUUUGUGUUGAAUUUUAUCAGAUGUUUUCAGCAUGCAUUGUGUUAUGUAUUUUUUUUUAAUUUGUUAAUCUGGUGAUUUCACCCAAUGGAAAGUGUUUGCAUUCCUGCUAUUCCACAUUAUUUUAUACCUUUUAAAAUCUACCCUGAGUUUUUUCUCAUGUAAACCAAACUUCUAACUUUUAAAAUGUUAGUUUAUUACUGUAGUUGCCUCAUAUUUUUAUAUAGGAGAUAAAAGAUUACUGGUAAAGCUG